CCACAGGCCAAGUGCGCUGUGCUCGAGGGGUGCCGGCCAGGCCUGAGCGAGCGAGCUAGCCAGCAGGCAUCGAGGGGGCGCGGCUGCCGUCCGGACGAGACAGGCGAACCCGACGCAGAAGAGUCCACCACCGGACAGCCAGGUAGCCGCCGCGUCCCUCGCACACGCAGAGUCGGGCGGCGCGGGGUCUCCCUUGCGCCCGGCCUCCGCCCUCUCCUCCUCUCCUUUCCCCUUCUUCUCGCUGUCCUCUCCUCUCUCGCUGCCCGCGUUUGCGCAGCCCCGGGCCAUGUCCGACGCGUCCCUCCGCAGCACAUCCACGAUGGAGCGUCUUGUCGCCCGUGGGACCUUCCCAGUACUAGUGCGCACCAGCGCCUGCCGCAGCCUCUUCGGGCCGGUGGACCACGAGGAGCUGAGCCGCGAGCUGCAGGCCCGCCUGGCCGAGCUGAACGCCGAGGACCAGAACCGCUGGGAUUACGACUUCCAGCAGGACAUGCCGCUGCGGGGCCCUGGACGCCUGCAGUGGACCGAAGUGGACAGCGACUCGGUGCCCGCGUUCUACCGCGAGACGGUGCAGGUGGGGCGCUGCCGCCUGCUGCUGGCGCCGCGGCCCGUCGCGGUCGCGGUGGCUGUCAGCCCGCCCCUCGAGCCGGCCGCUGAGUCCCUCGACGGCCUCGAGGAGGCGCCGGAGCAGCUGCCUAGUGUCCCGGUCCCGGCCCCGGCGUCCACCCCGCCCCCAGUCCCGGUCCUGGCUCCAGCCCCGGCCCCGGCUCCGGCUCCGGUCGCGGCUCCGGUCGCGGCUCCGGUCGCGGUCGCGGUCCUGGCCCCGGCCCCGGCCCCGGCUCCGGCUCCGGCUCCGGCCCCGGCUCCAGUCGCGGCCCCGGCCCCAGCCCCGGCCCCGGCCCCGGCCCCGGCCCCCGCCCCGGCCCCGGCCCCGGACGCGGCGCCUCAAGAGAGCGCCGAGCAGGGCGCGAACCAGGGGCAGCGCGGCCAGGAGCCUCUCGCUGACCAGCUGCACUCGGGGAUUUCGGGACGUCCCGCGGCCGGCACCGCGGCCGCCAGCGCCAACGGCGCGGCGAUCAAGAAGCUGUCCGGGCCUCUGAUCUCCGAUUUCUUCGCCAAGCGCAAGAGAUCAGCGCCUGAGAAGUCGUCGGGCGAUGUCCCCGCGCCGUGUCCCUCUCCAAGCGCCGCCCCUGGCGUGGGCUCGGUGGAGCAGACCCCGCGCAAGAGGCUGCGGUGAGCCAAAGCCCAAAGAGCCCCGAGGGAACCUGCCGGGGCAGCGGACGUUGGAAGGGCGCUGGGCCUCGGCUGGGACCGUUCAUGUAGCAGCAACCGGCGGCGGCUGCCGCAGAGCAGCGUUCGGUUUUGUUUUUAAAUUUUGAAAACUGUGCAAUGUAUUAAUAACGUCUUUUUAUAUCUAAAUGUAUUCUGCACGAGAAGGUACACUGGUCCCAAGGUGUAAAGCUUUAAGAGUCAUUUAUAUAAAAUGUUUAAUCUCUGCUGAAACUCAGUGCAAAAAAAAGAAAAAAGAAAAAAAAAAGGAAAAAAUAAAAAAACCAUGUAUAUUUGUACAAAAAGUUUUUAAAGUUAUACUAACUUAUAUUUUCUAUUUAUGUCCAGGCGUGGACCGCUCUGCCACGCACUAGCUCGGUUAUUGGUUAUGCCAAAGGCACUCUCCAUCUCCCACAUCUGGUUAUUGACAAGUGUAACUUUAUUUUCAUCGCGGACUCUGGGGAAGGGGGUCACUCACAAGCUGUAGCUGCCAUACAUGCCCAUCUAGCUUGCAGUCUCUUCGCGCUUUCGCUGUCUCUCUUAUUAUGACUGUGUUUAUCUGAAACUUGAAGACAAGUCUGUUAAAAUGGUUCCUGAGCCGUCUGUACCACUGCCCCGGCCCCUCGUCCGCCGGGUUCUAAAUAAAGAGGCCGAAAAAUGCUGCAA